GCUAUGCCCCGCCCCCUCCCCAGCCCCAGACACGGACCCCGCAGGCCAACUGGCUCCCUGCCCCUGCCCCCGCCCCUUGACAUCCCAGACUCCCUGGCUAUUUAAACAGAGAUGGGUGCCCCCAUCCGCACACUGUCCUUUGGCCACCGGACAUCAUGCCUCCCAAGAAGGAUGUUCCCGUGAAGAAACCAGCAGGGCCCUCCAUCUCCAAACCUGCUGCUAAGCCAGCAGCAGCAGGGGCUCCUCCAGCCAAGACCAAAGCUGAGCCAGCUGUCCCCCAGGCCCCUCAGAAAACCCAGGAGCCUCCAGUCGAUCUCUCCAAAGUGGUGAUCGAGUUUAACAAGGACCAGCUGGAGGAGUUCAAGGAGGCCUUCGAGCUGUUUGACCGAGUGGGGGAUGGCAAGAUCCUGUACAGCCAGUGUGGGGACGUGAUGAGGGCCCUGGGCCAGAACCCCACCAACGCCGAGGUGCUCAAGGUCCUGGGGAACCCCAAGAGUGAUGAGCUGAAGUCGCGGCGUGUGGACUUUGAGACUUUCCUGCCCAUGCUCCAGGCAGUGGCCAAGAACCGAGGCCAAGGCACAUAUGAGGACUACUUGGAGGGGUUUCGUGUGUUUGACAAGGAGGGGAACGGCAAAGUCAUGGGAGCAGAGCUCAGACAUGUUCUCACCACCCUUGGAGAGAAGAUGACUGAGGAGGAGGUGGAGACCGUUCUGGCAGGACACGAGGACAGCAACGGCUGCAUCAACUACGAGGCCUUCUUGAAACACAUCCUAAGCGUCUGAGUGCUGCAGAUCCAGUGGGGUCCGGACACUGGGCCCCGCAGGCGAAAGCACGUUCCAGCCACCAGGAGGCCACCUAUUGUUUCAAAAUAAAGACUGGGUUCCUCUCUUGG